GCGGCUGCUGCUUCCUCGGGCCAUUUUGCUGUGGAGCGGCGGGGAGGAGGAGCCGCCGAGGAGACCCCGGGCGAGGAGCUGCGAGCCGGAGGAGGCCGCGCGGACUCCGGGCUUUCCGCCGUCGCGGGGAUCUCGGGGGGCAAAGGGAUCGCCGGGGAGGGGGACCAGAGAGCCGCGCCCGCCGCGCGGAGCGCCCCUUCGCGUCCCCUGCACCAUGAGCUGGGGCACCGAGCUCUGGGAUCAGUUUGACAACUUAGAAAAACACACACAGUGGGGAAUUGAUAUUCUUGAGAAAUAUAUCAAGUUUGUGAAAGAAAGGACAGAGAUUGAACUCAGCUAUGCAAAGCAACUCAGGAAUCUUUCAAAGAAGUACCAACCUAAAAAGAACUCGAAGGAGGAAGAAGAAUACAAGUAUACGUCAUGUAAAGCUUUCAUUUCCAACCUGAACGAAAUGAAUGAUUACGCAGGGCAGCAUGAAGUUAUCUCCGAGAACAUGGCAUCACAGAUCAUUGUGGACUUGGCACGCUAUGUUCAGGAACUGAAACAGGAGAGGAAAUCAAACUUUCACGAUGGCCGUAAAGCACAGCAGCACAUCGAGACUUGCUGGAAGCAGCUUGAAUCUAGUAAAAGGCGAUUUGAACGCGAUUGCAAAGAGGCGGACAGGGCGCAGCAGUACUUUGAGAAAAUGGACGCUGACAUCAAUGUCACAAAAGCGGAUGUUGAAAAGGCCCGACAACAAGCUCAAAUACGUCACCAAAUGGCAGAGGACAGCAAAGCAGAUUACUCAUCCAUUCUCCAGAAAUUCAACCAUGAGCAGCAUGAAUAUUACCAUACUCACAUCCCCAACAUCUUCCAGAAAAUACAAGAGAUGGAGGAAAGGAGGAUUGUGAGAAUGGGAGAGUCCAUGAAGACAUAUGCAGAGGUUGAUCGGCAGGUGAUCCCAAUCAUUGGGAAGUGCCUGGAUGGAAUAGUAAAAGCAGCCGAAUCAAUUGAUCAGAAAAAUGAUUCACAGCUGGUAAUAGAAGCUUAUAAAUCAGGGUUUGAGCCUCCUGGAGACAUUGAAUUUGAGGAUUACACUCAGCCAAUGAAGCGCACUGUGUCAGAUAACAGCCUUUCAAAUUCCAGAGGAGAAGGCAAACCAGACCUCAAAUUUGGUGGCAAAUCCAAAGGAAAGUUAUGGCCGUUCAUCAAAAAAAAUAAGCUUAUGUCCCUUUUAACAUCCCCCCAUCAGCCUCCCCCUCCCCCUCCUGCCUCUGCCUCACCCUCUGCUGUUCCCAACGGCCCCCAGUCUCCCAAGCAGCAAAAGGAACCCCUCUCCCAUCGCUUCAACGAGUUCAUGACCUCCAAACCCAAAAUCCACUGCUUCAGGAGCCUAAAGCGUGGGACUCAGUCUUUCUGUUUUCACAAAGAACUCAUGAAGAGGACGAUAGGGAAACCCACGUAUGCCUUUGAGGCUAGGGACUAUGUUCUUUCUCUCAAGCUGGGUGCAACACCGGAGGAUUUCAGCAACCUCCCACCUGAACAAAGAAGGAAAAAGCUGCAGCAGAAAGUCGAUGAGUUAAAUAAAGAAAUUCAGAAGGAGAUGGAUCAAAGAGAUGCCAUAACAAAAAUGAAAGAUGUCUACCUAAAGAAUCCUCAGAUGGGAGACCCAGCCAGUUUGGAUCACAAAUUAGCAGAAGUCAGCCAAAAUAUAGAGAAACUGCGAGUAGAGACCCAGAAAUUUGAGGCCUGGCUGGCUGAGGUUGAAGGCCGGCUCCCAGCACGCAGCGAGCAGGCGCGCCGGCAGAGCGGACUGUACGACAGCCAGAACCCACCCACAGUCAACAACUGCGCCCAGGACCGUGAGAGCAGCCCAGAUGGCAGUUACACAGAGGAGCAGAGUCAGGAGAGUGAGAUGAAGGUGCUGGCCACGGAUUUUGACGACGAGUUUGAUGAUGAGGAGCCCCUCCCUGCCAUAGGGACGUGCAAAGCUCUCUACACAUUUGAAGGUCAGAAUGAAGGAACGAUUUCCGUAGUUGAAGGAGAAACAUUGUAUGUCAUAGAGGAAGACAAAGGCGAUGGCUGGACCCGCAUUCGGAGAAAUGAAGAUGAAGAGGGUUAUGUCCCCACUUCAUAUGUCGAAGUCUGUUUGGACAAAAAUGCCAAAGAUUCCUAGAGGGGAGUGCCUGCGAGCCUCGGGUGAGCCUUCCUGGAGGAGCCUCCGUCUGCUUGUUCCCACAGGCCUCCAGCGCCCUGCCCUGUGGACAGCCCACCCCUCCGCAGCCCCAUCCCUGCGGGGCGGUCUCUCUCUCUCUCCAGCAUGCUCCCUGCGGCCCUGCCCUCCCGCCCAGCCCGGGCCACCUCGUGGGGGACAAGUCUCGCCAGCGCCCACCCCCAUGGCUCGGGUCAGUCCUCAUCGCUCCCCCUCCCCACCCCGCGCAGGCCACUGAGACGGUGGGACACACGCCCCUACCUGCUCCUUCCUGGGCCCUCAGUCCACCCGGGCUCGUCCUGGCAGCCCUUCCGCGCUUCACACAGUGCCUUUUGUGAAAGUGUCAUCACGGGUCCCCUGAGGAGACAAGGCAGGUCCAGCGCACAUCAGGCGGACUGAGCACUCGAUGUCAUCCGUGUCGAUGUCAUCCGUGUGUCCCAGACUGUCUGCUGUAGAAAACACUUCCUCCUCUCCUGAGUCUGUGAAGUCCUCAGUGGUCCUUUUUGGAUUCUAGGCUUGCACCUCAUACUAAACAUUGACCCUUUCACUAUGCCCUCAACCUGGGAGCAUCUGGCAGGCAGGGGGGCAGGUACACACACACCCACAGGCACACCCACCAGUACACACGCGUGCGCAUACACACAUUUUGGUUUGACGCCCUGUUUUCAGUGGCCUGGGGAGGUCCACACUGGAAGUCGAAUUCCAGCUCGCCUUGUUGACUCGCCUGUGUCCACCGGCCAUGAGGAGCCCACGCCUGUCCUCCCCAUCACUUUCCUGUCCCUGAGAACUGUAGAUCAUGCGCUUGUGAGCGAGGCCCUCCCCUCUGCACCAGCUCAUUGCAAAGCGAACAUCCUCUCCUUUCCAGGAGCCCCAGGAUUAGCAUCUGAAAAGGGUAGCACUUCCUUUUUUGUUGUUGUUUUUUUUUUUUUUUUGAGACGGGAGUCUCGCUCUAUUGUUCAGACUGGAGUGCAGUGGCAUGAUCUCGGCUCACUACAACCUCCACCUCCUGGGUUCCAGCGAUUCUCCUGCCUCAGCCUCCCAAAUAGCUGUGAUUACAGGCGUGCACCACCACGCCCGGCUAAUGUUUGUAUUUUUAGUAGAGACAGGGUUUCACCGUGUUGGUCAGGCUGGUCUCAAACUCCUGACCUCAGGUGAUCCGCCCGCCUCAGCCUCCCAAAGUGCUGAGAUUACAGGUGUGAGCUACCGCACCCCGCCGAGGUUAGCACUUUCAUCACCAAAGACCCCGUGCCUCUCGUGGUCCUUUGAGGGAUCCCGCCGCCACCACCCUUGUAUUUUAUCACGUGCUCUUCAGGGCAUGUGGAAUUCGUUGAGUUUGCUUUUAGAGCCAAGUUUCUUUCCCUGUGUGGGUUUUUGAGGAAAACCUGAGGUCCCCUAAUCUGUGGCCACCACCCCCCCCCCCCGCCACGCCUUAGAGCAGAGCAGCCCCUCCUCUCAUUUGGUGCAGAAACAGUCAAGAGGAACCAUUGGCCUAGAGCUCCUGUGACCGAGAGCGCCACGGAAGCCUGGGGAUGACGUCGGGCAGCUUUAUUCUUUGCUUGGCUUUGGUAACUAGGUGGUCCCCUCAAGCAUCCUCAGUUCCUCUUGCUGUUUAUGAAUCUAAGACAAGGAAGUCCUAUAGAAGCCAAAGGGACAGGGACGGAAAGGACAGGUCCCAAGGGAUGGGGCUGUCUUUACUUGUGGAAACCAGGAAAUUGCUCCUCUCAGCCAACCAAGGUUGACCACACACCACCCUUCCGGAGCAGCUCAGUCAGCCCUCGGGGACGAGAAACCACAAGCGCAGAGACGCUGAGGCCCAGGCAGGUGAAGAGGAAGUGGCUUUGGGUUUUUAAAGUAGGUGAGCGUGAGCCUCUCUGACUGCUUCUUCCCCGGGGGGGACUGCAAACCGCUCAGGGUUGCGGCAGAGCCAUGGACUUCCGGUCCCUGCAACGGGUGACCUAAGCGUGGUGCACCCAUCAGUCACGCAGGAGGACUGACUUGACAGACGAAAGACAAGCCCGGAUGACACAGGGUGAGAAGAGUCAGGGCCGCACCUCUGUCCCUGCAAACCAACAGGUGCAUGGUGAGUGUGGCAGUCCCCACAGCUCCACAAUGGGCUCCCCCGCCAACGGGGACGACAGGGAUCUUCAGGAACUUCUGACCUCACCAAGUCAAGUGGACCACUCUCCACUCCACGAGGAUGUGAAACGGUUCUUUAAAAUGGGAUUUUAGAGCCUCGGGAAUGCAUGUGCGUCACAUCUUUCAUAUUAUGGGUCAGGAUAGAUUCAUUUCUUGCAACAUAGUGGAAAAGAUAUAAGCUGCAGUAAUUUGCUCUUUGAAUGACCGUCACCCCCAGUAUAGGAUAUGCUUGUAUCCCCCCGUCACUCCUCCGCCUGUUUUUUAAACUUUUCCACCACCUGCGUCCAAAAAGAAUGUUAUAGCGAGUGCUCUUAAAUGUUGAACCUGGGUGUUGCUUCCGGGCCAGUCUGCGUGGCUCCAUGAAAAGCUCACUGCUGCCCCAGCCGGGCUUCUUAGAGGAGGUCAGUUGUCCUAUGUAUCAUCAUUUACUCUGGGAAUCCUACUGUGAAAUCAUGUCUGUAUUUUUCUGGAGCAGUUCACAUAGAGUAGAAUGUGGAAUUUCCCGUGAACGUCUCCUUCCUCCCCCGUAUCUGCCGCCUGUCACUUCGCCACCGUGCUAGAAUACUGUUGUGUUGUAAGAUGACUAAUUUUAAAAGAACCUGCCCUGAAAAGUUCUUAGAAACGCAGUGAAAGGGAGGAACUUGUCCUUUACCCAGUUUUUCCUUUGUAGGAUGGGAAAGUAUAAAAAGGCACAGAAGGUUGUCAUGGGCUGUUCCUUGGGGGUUUUUAUCCUGCUCACCGUGGAGAUAAGCCUGCGGCUUGUCUAACCAGCGCAGCGCAAAGGUCUCGAUGCCUUUUGGUAACAUCCGUCAUUGCAGAAGAAAGUUUACACGACGUCAAAAAGUGACGUUCAUGCUAAGUGUUUUUCCAGAAAUAUUGGUUUCAUGUUUCUUAUUGGCUCUGCCUCCUGUGCUUAUAUCAUCCAAAAACUUUUUAAAAAGGUCCAGAAUUCUAUUUUAACCUGAUGUUGAGCACCUUUAAAAUGUUCGUAUGUGUGUUGCACUAAUUCUAAACUUUGGAGGCAUUUUGCUGUGUGAGGCCGAUCGCCACUGUAAAGGUCCUAGAGUUGCCUGUUUGUCUCUGGAGAUGGAAUUAAACCAAAUAAAGAGCUUCCACUGGAGGCUUGUAUUGACCUUGUAACUAUAUGUUAAUCUCGUGUUAAAAUAAAAUAUAACUUGUG